GCGUCUGCCGCAGCAACGGGGUGCGGCAGGGUGGGGAACGCGGGAGCGGGGCCAGCUCCCAGGAAAGCUGGUCUGCGAGCGGCCCCUGCCCGGCUCCCAGGUCCCUGCGCGACCCCGCCCUUCCCGAGACCCCAGCCGGGCUGCCGCCCGCGUCCCGGAAGCUCCAGCCUGAACCAUGUUUUUCACUUGUGGCCCAAAUGAGGCCAUGGUGGUCUCCGGGUUCUGCCGAAGCCCCCCAGUCAUGGUGGCUGGAGGGCGUGUCUUUGUCCUGCCCUGCAUCCAACAGAUCCAGAGGAUCUCUCUCAACACACUGACCCUCAAUGUCAAGAGUGAAAAGGUUUACACUCGCCAUGGGGUCCCCAUCUCAGUCACUGGCAUUGCCCAGGUAAAAAUCCAGGGGCAGAACAAGGAGAUGUUGGCGGCCGCCUGUCAGAUGUUCCUGGGGAAGACGGAGGCUGAGAUUGCCCACAUUGCCCUGGAGACGUUAGAGGGCCACCAGAGGGCCAUCAUGGCCCACAUGACUGUGGAGGAGAUCUAUAAGGACAGGCAGAAAUUCUCAGAACAGGUUUUCAAAGUGGCCUCCUCAGACCUGGUCAACAUGGGCAUCAGUGUGGUUAGCUACACUCUGAAGGACAUUCACGAUGACCAGGACUAUUUGCACUCUUUGGGGAAGGCUCGAACAGCUCAAGUCCAAAAAGAUGCACGGAUUGGAGAAGCAGAGGCCAAGAGAGAUGCUGGGAUCCGGGAAGCUAAAGCCAAGCAGGAAAAGGUGUCUGCUCAGUACCUGAGUGAGAUCGAGAUGCAGGUGGCCAAGACUAAGCAGCAGAUUGAGGAGCAGCGGGUGCAGGUGCAGGUGGUGGAGCGGGCCCAGCAGGUGGCAGUGCAGGAGCAGGAGAUCGCCCGGCGGGAGAAGGAGCUGGAGGCCCGGGUGCGGAAGCCAGCGGAAGCGGAGCGCUACAAGCUGGAGCGCCUAGCCGAGGCAGAGAAGUCCCAACUAAUUAUGCAGGCGGAGGCAGAAGCCGCGUCUGUGCGGAUGCGUGGGGAAGCUGAGGCCUUUGCCAUAGGGGCCCGAGCCCGAGCCGAGGCUGAGCAGAUGGCCAAGAAGGCAGAAGCCUUCCAGCUGUACCAAGAGGCUGCUCAGCUGGACAUGCUGCUAGAGAAGCUGCCCCAGGUGGCAGAGGAGAUCAGUGGUCCCUUGACUUCAGCCAAUAAGAUCACACUGGUGUCCAGCGGCAGUGGGACCAUGGGGGCAGCCAAAGUGACUGGGGAAGUACUGGACAUUCUAACUCGCCUGCCAGAGAGUGUGGAAAGACUCACAGGCGUGAGCAUCUCCCAGGUGAAUCACAAGCCUUUGAGAACAGCCUGAGCCUUCAGCCCUCACAGAUGCCCAGCCUCAUAGCUGAAGUUGCCUGAAUGAUCCUCCUGUUGCAUGUAACCCACUGGCCUCCCUGAGCAUGUCCAUUGACAGUGAGGUCCCACCCCUCAUCUCUCCUUGCCAAAUAGUUUGUGCCUUGUCUUGAAGGGGGUUGCUCCCCUUGCCAACCUCACACUGCUAUGAUUGCCAACUCCAGCGGUCCCAUGUCAGCCUUCUGAUGAUCCCACUCCACCCCACCUCAACUUAUUUAACUUCCUAAUUAAAUCAGACUGUUUGAGCCUGUUGUCUAGAAUAUUUUCCUGACCAAGACUGAGGGAUGGGCUGGAGGUUUUCAACUUUGCUACCCAAAUAAAUUGCUGUAAGUAAGUACUAAUAAAACAGAAGCAACUGGAAAUUAA